GUCCCCAAGCAGCCACCCAGCUCCGACAUGGCCCAGCCGGUCCACAGCCUCUGCUCCGCCUUUGGCCUCCAGUGCUGCCUCCUCUUCCUUCUAGCUUCUUGGGGGGCAGGUGCUACUACAUUCCAAGAAUAUCAGAAAACUGGGGAACUCUCAACAUCCGAUCACAUAUUUCCCCUCACUCCAGGCCUUGUUUAUAGUAUCCCUUUUGAUCACAUUGUUCUGCAUUCAGGACAAAGACCUCCAGAGCUCCCUAAAUCUACAGAAAUCCAUGAGCAAAAACGCCACUGCAACACCACACGCCAUUCUAAGCCAACUGACAAGCCUACAGGCAACUCCAAAACUAUAGACCACAAAAGCUCUACAGAUAAUCAUGAGGCUCCUCCCACUUCUGAAGAAAACUCCAGCAACCAAGGGAAAGACCCAAUGAUCCGGAACCAGCGCUCUGUUGAUCCUGCUGACUCCACUACCACACAUAAAGAAUCCGCUGGAAAAAAACAUAUAACGCCAGCACCCAAGAGCAAAAUAAACUGUCGUAAGUCCACAACAGGCAAAUCAACGGUAACAAGAAAAUCAGAUAAAACUGGAAGACCUUUGGAAAAGUCCAUGAGUACUUUGGAUAAGACAAGUACCAGCUCACAUAAGACUACAACUUCCUUCCACAACUCAGGCAAUUCACAGACCAAGCAAAAAAGCACAUCUUUUCCAGAAAAAAUCACAGCAGCCUCAAAAACAACAUACAAGACCACAGGAACCCCAGAAGAGUCAGAAAAAACUGAAGAUUCCAGAACAACAGUUGCCUCAGACAAGCUCCUGACAAAAACUACAAAAAACAUACAAGAGACCAUAUCAGCCAAUGAGCUCACACAAUCUCUAGCAGAGCCUACAGAACAUGGAGGAAGGACAGCCAAUGAGAACAACACACCAUCCCCAGCAGAGCCUACAGAAAAUAGAGAAAGGACAGCCAAUGAGAACACCACACUAUCCCCAGCAGAGCCUACAGAAAAUAGAGAAAGGACAGCCAAUGAGAACACCGCACCAUUCCCAGCAGGGCCUACAGAAAAUAGAGAAAUGACAGCCAAUGAGAAUACCACACUAUUCCCAGCAGAGCCUACAGAACAUGGAGAAAGGACAGCCAAUGAGAACACCACACCAUCCCCAGCAGAGCCUACAGAACAUGGAGAAAGGACAGCCAAUGAGAACACUACACCAUCCCCAGCAGAGCCUACAGAACAUGGAGAAAGGACCCCAUUUGCCAAUGACAAAACCACAUCAUCCUCAGCAGAGUCUACAGAACAUGGAGAAAGGACCCCACUGGCCAACGAGAACACCACACCAUCCCCAGCAGAGCCUACAGAAAAUAGAGAAAGGACAGCCAAUGAGAACACCACACCAUCCCCAGCAGGGCCUACAGAAAACAGAGAAACGACAGCCAACGAGAAGACCACACUAUCCCCAGUAGAGCCUACAGAAAAUAGAGAAACAACAGCCAAUGAGAAGACCACACCAUCCCCAGCAGAGCCUACAGAAAAUGGACAAAGGACCCCAUUUGCCAAUGAGAAAACCACAUCAUCCUCAGCAGAGCCUACAGAACACGGAGAAAGGACCCCACUGGCCAAUGAGAACACCACACCAUCCCCAGCAGAGCCUACAGAAAAUAGAGAAAGGACAGCCAAUGAGAAGACCACACCAUCCCCAGCAGAGCCUACAGAAAAUGGAGACAGGACUCCUUUGGCCAAUGAGAAGACCACGCCAUCUCUAGCAGAGCCUACAGAAAAUGGACAAAGGACCCCAUUUGCCAAUGAGAAGACCACAUCAUCCUCAGCAGAGCCUACAGAACACGAAGAAAGGACUCCACUGGCCAAUGAGAACACCACACCAUCCCCGGCAGAGCCUACAGAAAAUAGAGAAAGGACAGCCAAUGAGAACACCACACCAUCCCCAGCAGGGCCUACAGAAAAUAGAGAAAUGACAGCCAACGAGAAGACCACACUAUUCCCAGCAGAGCCUACAGAAAAUAGAGAAAGGACAGCCAAUGAGAAGACCACAUCAUCCCCAGCAGAGCCUACAGAAAAUGGACAAAGGACCCCAUUUGCCAAUGAGAAAACCACAUCAUCCUCAGCAGAGCCUACAGAACACGGAGAAAGGACCCCACUGGCCAAUGAGAACACCACACUAUCCCCAGCAGGGCCUACAGAAAAUAGAGAAAGGACAGCCAAUGAGAAGACCACACCAUUCCCAGCAGAGCCUACAGAAAAUAGAGAAAGGACAGCCAAUGAGAACACCACACCAUCCCCAGCACAGCCUACAGAAAAUGGAGACAGGACUCCAUUGGCCAAUGAGAAGACCACACCAUCUCUAGCAGAGCCUACAGAAAAUGGAAAAAGGACCCCAUUUGCCAAUGAGAAGACCACAUCAUCCUCAGCAGAGCCUACAGAACACGCAGAAAGGACUCCACUGGCCAAUGAGAACACCACAUCAUCCCCAGCAGAGCCUACAGAAAAUAGAGAAAGGACAGCCAAUGAGAAGACCACACAAUUCCCAGCAGAGCCUACAGAAAAUAGAGAAAGCACAGCCAAUGAGAAGACCACACCAUUCCCAGCAGAGCCUACAGAAAAUAGAGAAUGGACAGCCAAUGAGAACACCACACUAUCCCCAGCAGAGCCUACAGAACAUGAAGAAAUGACCCCAUUGGCC